AGCGAGCGAGACUGCGCUGGCGAGGAGGAGCCGCGCGAGCGGCGGCUGCUGGGCGCUUCCCCGCGCUGCUGGGCGCUCGGCGCCUCCGCGGCCCCGGCUCCCGGCCGCAGCUUCCUCGCGCGCGCGGGGCGCCGGGCGCGGGGCCCGGGCUGGCUUCGCGGAAGGGUUUGCUGAACUAACUCCAAGCUGGUGUGCCUAGCGUCCGCGCGGCUGCCGGCCCAAGAGCUGGAGUCACCAUGGCGGCCGGAGUUGCGGCCUGGCUGCCUUUUGCCCGGGCUGCGGCCAUCGGGUGGAUGCCGGUGGCCAACUGCCCCAUGCCCCUGGCCCCGGCCGACAAGAACAAGCGGCAGGAUGAGCUGAUUGUCCUCAACGUGAGUGGGCGGAGGUUCCAGACCUGGAGGACCACGCUGGAGCGCUACCCGGACACCCUGCUGGGCAGCACGGAGAAGGAGUUCUUCUUCAACGAGGACACCAAGGAGUACUUCUUCGACCGGGACCCCGAGGUGUUCCGCUGCGUGCUCAACUUCUACCGCACGGGGAAGCUGCACUACCCGCGCUACGAGUGCAUCUCUGCCUACGACGACGAGCUGGCCUUCUACGGCAUCCUCCCGGAGAUCAUCGGGGACUGCUGCUACGAGGAGUACAAGGACCGCAAGAGGGAGAACGCCGAGCGGCUCAUGGACGACAACGACUCGGAGAACAACCAGGAGUCCAUGCCCUCGCUCAGCUUCCGCCAGACCAUGUGGCGGGCCUUCGAGAACCCCCACACCAGCACGCUGGCCCUGGUCUUCUACUACGUGACUGGCUUCUUCAUCGCUGUCUCGGUCAUCACCAACGUGGUGGAGACGGUGCCGUGCGGCACGGUCCCGGGCAGCAAGGAGCUGCCGUGCGGGGAGCGCUACUCGGUGGCCUUCUUCUGCCUGGACACGGCGUGCGUCAUGAUCUUCACCGUGGAGUACCUCCUGCGGCUCUUCGCGGCUCCCAGCCGCUACCGCUUCAUCCGCAGCGUCAUGAGCAUCAUCGACGUGGUGGCCAUCAUGCCCUACUACAUCGGUCUGGUCAUGACCAACAACGAGGACGUGUCCGGCGCCUUCGUCACGCUCCGGGUCUUCCGCGUCUUCAGGAUCUUCAAGUUUUCCCGCCACUCCCAGGGCCUGCGGAUCCUGGGCUACACACUGAAGAGCUGUGCCUCCGAACUGGGCUUUCUUCUCUUCUCCCUCACCAUGGCCAUCAUCAUCUUUGCCACUGUGAUGUUUUAUGCCGAGAAGGGCUCCUCGGCCAGCAAGUUCACAAGCAUCCCUGCCUCGUUUUGGUACACCAUUGUCACCAUGACCACACUGGGAUGAAAGGGGGAGUCAGCACAGCCGGUGUCAGAGGAAAGCAAGUGUGGAAAACCUUCCAGGCCAGGAGGGUGCUGCCUGAGGCAUCCACCCUAACUUCUCUGAAGUCCUGUUUAGUCACAAAAUUCAUGCAACCAGUGCUUAUUAUAAGCAAUGUUUUCCACAUUGUCUAGUUUAACAAAGCAGUUCUUCAACUUUCUGGUUUCAGAAAAAUUACCAAGAAUCCCAAUGACCUUUUAUUUCUGUGGAAUAUGUAGGGUUAGAAAUUUAGCACUGUGAAUUUUUAAAUGUUUUUAAAUACUUGUUUAUUAAUUCAUUUUAAAAUAACAUAUCCCAUUACACAUUAAAAUACAUUUUAUGGAAAAUAUAUUUCCAAAAUUUAAAAAACCUGGAAGAGUGGCAUUGUUUUAUAUUUUUGAAAAUCUCUUUAAUGAAUUAGAAGACAGCUGGAUUCUCACAUCUGCAUCUGCAUUCAAUCUGUUGAUAUCUGUGGUUUUGUUUGUAGUAUAUAAAGAAAACCAGCCUUACACAGCAGGGCGCAGACUCAGGGCUGAAAACCUAAGGAGCCACCCACUCUUGAGGUCCUGCAAGGGUAGGGUUGUCCCUGAGAGUGAGGGCCUCCUUAAAUUUUGCACUCAAGGGCCCUGCCUUGUCUCACUUGGGUCCUAGCCUGGUCAGGCGGGAAAAACCACUGGCUUAAGAUAUGCUCCAGGGAUUGCAAGGAGGGUCUCCUACCUGGAAUAUAGGCCAAGAUACAAAGUCAUGAAUGAGUGCAAGGUCUGAGGAACCGCACUGGGCCCAGAUCUGAGCAAGCCUUUUAUGCUGCAUGAAGAAACAGGCCUUUAUCUGGAAGGCUAUGAGGAGCCACAGAAGAGUCAAGCAGGGAGUGAUGGGAUCAGAUUUGCAUUUUUAGAUUCAUUCAUUUGUUUGUUAAUUGAUAUGUAUUGAGCUCCUAUUGUGUGCUGGGCACUGGGAAUAACAGUGAACAGAGGUUUCUGUUCUCAUAGAGCUCACAUUGUGGGGAAGCAGAUAAUAAAUGAAUAUAGAUCUAUAGAUCCACGCUGCUGACGUAGAAAGAUGGACCGGAGGAUAAUUAGAUGGAGGGGAGAAGAGUUCAGGCAGUUGGAACAAUAGCCACCGAAGAGUCGAUAGUGAACAGAAUGGCAGUAGAAAUGGAGUAGGCGAGAACAUGAGAGGGUCAACGCAACACUAAGGAUGCAGCCACCAGUGCUACCUGGGAGAAAUCAAAGGUGAUGCCCAGCUUCCACCUCAGGCAGUCGGGUCUACUGUGAUUUGGGCACCCAACAGGAGAAGCAUUUGGGGGGGAUAAUCCAUUUUGUUAGCAACAACACGUUGAGUUUGAAGAGCCUGAGAGGAUGGGGUCAUUUGGGUGGAGAUGUCCAGUGAGGUGCUGGGUUAUAUAGGUCUGACCUUCAGAAUGGAGGGCGGGACGAGGGAUUGGAUUGUGAGAGCUGUCAACCAUUCAGGAGGUGAGUGGAUAAUGGCAUUCAGGAACAGUGCUCAGAGUGAGACCGGGGACACUUAUUCCUGCCACUCUUCCUCAAAGUCAGCGUAUCUGAAAUCAGAUUUGUAGUCUUUCCCCCAUCCCUGAAGACCAUUCUCCAACUUAAUUAAUGACACCAACAACCUUGCAUCUAUUAGAGCUAGAAACCUGAGGUUCAGCCUGGAUGCUGUCUCCUGCUCAGCUCCCACCUACCAUGGCCUCAUGAUCUACCAGCUCUCUCACCUUGUCUGCCACACCCCCAAACUGCUGCUUCACUCUUCCAGCCCAUUUCUUCUGUCUGGAAGGCCCAUUUGAAUUGUCCCUACCACUCUCAUCAGAAACAUCCACCUAAGAAAUUCCUACUCAUUCUUCAAGACCUGCUCUAGCAUCCCCUUUCAUUUUAGGUCGCCCCAUAUCCCUGCAACCGCACAACCACACAGCCUGAGACAUAAUUGUUCGUCCUCUUUAGUUUCCAAUUUCGUGACCAUGACUCUGUUUAACACUCAUAACACUGCAGCGCAACCAUUUGCUCACAUGACUUUCUCUCUUACUACAGUGAAACUCACAUGACAGAAGAAAAUAGAUUGAAUUGUCUUUGUAGCAUUUGUUUCGCGGGUGGCUCCUGAAUGAAUGCUAAGACCUCAACCAGAUGGGUUUACUGAGAAAGGCAGAAAGCCAGGACCAGAACUAGGAAAGUGACCCUCCCCAGCUAGUCUACCCAGCAUCUAGGUCAAUGGGAAUCCAGUCUGGGGUAUAAGCAAGACCACAGUGGGCUGUGAGCAUGGUAAAACUCAAGCAAAUAGGAAGCAGUACCUUGGUUCCAGGGGCCUCAUGCAGCAGUGGCUGGGGUGGCUAAUGGACGGUGGCAACAGCAAAGAGCAAAGCAGUGGAUCCGAGUAAAAGGACAGAGAGCUGAGCAGAGCUGGUGGCAGGAUGGGGGGUCUCUCCAUACCCCAGCACACCAGGCAUAUGGUGCAUAGCAGAUCCCAGAGCUCACCUGGGGUAACAGUGAAGAUAGGUCCUACUCAGGAUGGUCCUGGGGCUGGGGAUUACUGAGCCUUCUUGAGUGAAAUGCCUCUGAGCCUUCCAGCCAGAAGGGUUUGUCCAGGUAGCAGUGAUAACACCUGUUGUUUGUGGGGACAGUGAGGAAUCUGGCCUAACUAGGGCAAAGGGUUUGCACUGGUGACUAAUGGGAGAUGCAGUUGAAUAGUAUAAACAUACUCUUUUUUAUCUAUUCAAUCAAGAGAAGUAACAGCUACAAACCCAGACAGAAGCCCAUAAAAUGAGACAAUUAUUUUGAGAUGGCCACAGGUAGACGGAAGUAAAGGUUAGAUCCUAUCCUUGUUCACAAAGACACGGGUAAAUUGUGUGAAUACCAAGCUCUGUGAGGAAAGGCAAAAGCUUUGUAAGACUUGCUGCCCACACCAAACACAGCCCUGAGCCCAGCGAACAUAGAUGGAGCUGUCAUCACAGGGAGUUGCUUCCCACUCCAGAUAUGCCCCGUCAGUGCUGCUGCUUGGGGCAGAGCGGCAAGCCUUGGGCUCAGAAAUGCUGCUUCCAGAAGCCCAUAAACAAAAGGCAGCUGUCUGCUCUCCCUCUUCCAAGAAUUCUUAGCAAGUACCAGUUUUCAUUAAUGGGAAGCAAAUCCACUAAUGGCAUUCAGGAACAGCGCUCAGAGUGAGACCAGGGGCCUCACUCUUUUCUCUUAUUCUCUAUCCCAGGGCUCUAGAAAAAAGAUAGCAGGGCCCCCUGCUGCAUCCCUUGGAGCCCCAUUUCUUCUUCCUCUGCUCAGCCCUGGCUGGUCAUCAGGGUAUCCUGGAGCAGGAGGGAGAGAAGAGCUCCAUCAUAUCAACAUUCCUCACCCAGGAGGGCAGAGAGCAAAGUGAAGAUAAUAUACAGACUUUGGAAUUGCACAGGCUUGCCAGUUGGAGAUGUGUAACCUCUCUAAGACUCAGUUUCCUCAUAUAUAACAUGGUUGUAAUAACAGUACCAGCCUCAUAGGAUUGUUACAAGAUCUUUACAUGUAAAGUUCUUAGUCCAGCGCUUGGCAUGUACUUACUGCUCAAUAUAAGUUAGCUGCUGCCACUGUGAUUAUUAUCUGCUCCUGGCCCUCAUUGGAAUUCCAGUGCUUAACUUGCGAUGGAGGCAGGUAACAAAAUUCUGUCUGCUUAGUGUCCUGGGACCCCUGGCAAUAUCUCGGAUUCCUGUGCAAGAUGUGUUCCUGCAUCGUGAACCCACUGAAAGUCAAGGGACCAAGUGCUGGGGGUCACAGGACAUGGGUGUGCUUACUUGGGCUCCACCCCUAGGCUGCACCAGCUGCCUUACCUCUCCUCUUGGCACUUGUAUUUCCUGUCUCUGCUUUCACUCAUGGGCAAUUCCAACCGUCAUCUGCGUACACAUCUGUUCUCAUAGCAACAUACACUACAUAUGCAUGUCUUCCAGCUUUGCUGUACACUUAGGCAAACUACUUAACCACUCUGUGCCUUAGUUUUCCCAUCCAAAAACUGGAAAUAAUCAUACAGGCUAAGUAUUCCUAAUCCCAAAAUUCCAAAUCUGAAACACUUCAAAAUCUGAAACUUUUUGAUUGCUGACAUGAUGCACAAAGAAAAUGCUCAGUGGAGUAUUGGAUUUGGGAUUAGGGAUGCUCAACCAUAAGUUUAAUGUGAAUAUUCCAAAAUCUAAAGAAGUCCAAAAUCCAAAACACUUCUGGUCCCAAGCCUUUUGGAUAAGGGAUACUCAACCUGUAGUACCAGCCUCAUAGGGUUGUUGGAGAUUAAACCAGGUAAUUAAUGUGAAGCACUUAGAACAAAGAUCAGCAUAUUUCAGGUGAUCAUUAAACAUUAGCUGUUAUUAUCAUGACUAUUAUUAUUAUUAUAAUAGAAACUUCACAUCUCCCAGUAGUAGGGAUUUUGCUCUGAGGCGCCACUGUCCUAUUGAAACCCUGAAUGAACUCUUCAGCCUUAGGAAACAUUCAGAAACCAUGAACUCGUUGACAUAGUAAACCACCUGUGAGUGACCUCUUGACCCAAAUAAGCAUUAAACGUAGAAAGAUUAAGAGCCCUGAGCCAAACCUGAGGGCCUGAGACCUGCAUGUCUUUGUAUGUUCAUGGCAGAUGAUGGUGGGUGUGUGCACAUACAAAGGAAGAGCACGUGGCAUGAGAGCAGACACGUGUCCUAGACCUGAAAGUUGAAAGUCAAGGUUUUAUGGUCCAUGGCUGCACACUCUAAAAGAAAACAUCUCACAAGGAGUGAGAGACUCUAAAAAUGAAAUUAGAACAAGAAAUUCACAUAUACUUCCAACAAGGAAGAAAAAUGAGACAUCUAAAGAAAUCAAUGUGGCUACCUGGGAAACCUCUAAUGAACCUAGAUUUUAAAAGCCAAAAACUAUAUUUACAGCAAAUAUUGGAUAAAUUGUUAAUAUCUUUAAUAUAUAAAGAGCUCGUGCAAAUCAGUAAUGAAACCCCUAAGGCAAAAUAGAAAAGUGAAUCAAGGAUGUAAUAAACAAUUCGCUAAAGAAGAAAUAAAGCUAGCUUUCCAACAGAUGGAAAAUCUUCAAUCUUACUAGUAAUCACAAUGAAAAUUCAAACAACUAGAUAGCUAUUUUUGGCUUGCAAAUUAGCAAAGACUUUGAUUUUGAUUUUUAGUGAGUACCCUACCCAAUGCUGGUGAGGGUGCAGCAAAAUAGUCUCAUUCAAACACUGCACGUGGGAUAUGGCACUCAGGAGAGUCACUUCUUGGAUCUCUCCCGAGGAAAUAGUGCUACUUUAGAAAUACUGUUAUUAAUAAUAUUUGUAUAAGCAAAAAUUAGAAAGAAUCAGAAUGCAUCCAUGUAGAAUAAUGCUUAUUAUUAUUUCAGAUGGUAGUGUGGGAAAAAGCAGGAGACAAAAUUAUACACACAAUAUGUAAGUAUGAUUUAAAAGAAAAACAAGACUAGAAGAAAACAAAAUACAAUGAUGGUAUCUUUGGGUGGUGGAAGCAUGGAUGAUUUGUUUAAUUCUUUCUGCAUUUUUGCUUGGUGAUCAGAUUUCUUACAAUGAUUGUGCAUUACUUUUAUUAUGGAAAAAAUAAACUUUAUUGUAAUACUGGAGAUGUAGAAAGAAUAGGAAGAGAGCUCACACCAUGGAAGACAAAUCCAACAGACAAGUGCAUUCCUGUGGUCCAGUGUCAGGGAUCCUUAAAGCUUCAAGUGGAUCUGGCUUAUGGGCAGAGCUACAAUCAACAUGAGGAACUUGUACUGUGUGAACAUGGCAGAGAUUAGUGUGCUGCCUGGGAAGUAUGUGCGGCAUUUAAGAACAACCUGAGCUGAUGGGCCAUUGUGCCACAAAGUAGGAAGAAUCCUGGACCUCGGACAUAUGGGUCAAAAAAUACUAACAGUGUCAUAGACAUCACUGAUAUCGGUGAUCACCAGCCUAGUCCACCACUUCCCAAAGUGUGGACCCUGGAUCACUGGUGGGCUCAGAAUGACUCCAAAUAAUGCUGAAGCAGUUUAGGUGGUGUAUGGACAUGGAAUUAUUAUUUUUAAGUUUUUCUUCUUGAAUUUUCUUUCAAUCUUUCUAGUGAUACCAAAGAGAAGUCUUAAUUUGAUGCUAGGAUAUCUUUAACACUGUUACUGAAAUGUCAGGGGUUUGGUCUGGGUCCUGCUGCUUGCCACACAGAAAGCCAAUCACUGAGACAACAAGUGCUGCCAGGGAAGAAGGCUUUAUUCAGGGCUGCAACCAAGGAGAAUGGGAGAUCAGUCUCAAAUCCAUCUCCUCAACCAACUGAAGUUAGGGAUUUAUAUAUAACAGCAGGAAAGAAAUGUAACUAUGUGUGGAAAAACAGGAUUUAAGGAGGGGUAAGGAAGAGGGGUUGGAAAACAGGAAUCGCCAUGGAUGAGGGGUCUGGCAUCUCAUGUCUGGAUGCAGUGAUCUGGUGAGUUUCAGAUCCCUGAUACUCUCUGGGAGGCCUGAGGGUCGGUUUUCUGAGGAUGGGACUCAAAUAAGAUAAAUGUAAGUUUCGAGCUUUAAGAUCAAGAGGGUCCAUUUCUAUGUUUAUCCAAAAAACAGUAAACAUCAGUUUGAUGGAACAGUUGGGCCGGUUUCAACACCUCUUUAACCCUUGCUCAUCUCCCUUUCUAACCAAGUAGGAGCAGGCUUCAGGCUCAGUUCCUUAAGCAGACAACAGCAUCUGGCUAGAAUUCAGUAAUGCAAGUGGUGUGUGGGUAUGGCAGAAUCACCAGGGCAGAAGAAGAAUUAAAGUAGUUUGGUAAACACUGAACUAGUCCAGAACUUUGGGCAUCUGGGACAUAAAGGGUCAGGGAGGGAGGGUGAUUUGCUGCAAGUCAACCAACUGGUCAACACCAGACCAAGCCUGGUCUCCCUGCUUCAACUACCGGCCCUUUCCCCAAGCUCUUCUGCUCUCCACGUGGAGCUGUCAGUAUUUCUCCACUUUCCUUCAAAAAGCAGACCUAGUACUAUCUUGUUCUUUGCUGUCUUUGUUAUUUCUUGUUUGAGCUUUUUUUUUUUUUUUUUGGAGUUGGAGAAGGCAUGGGAUCAUGCUAUUAGCAUAACUAAAAAUGUUUUUAGUUUGCCUCUGCAUUUUCCCCAAGCCUCAGCUUUUCCUAAAAAUCCAGCAUCUUCUGCAUCCUUCCCUGGGGACCACACUACUCCUCAGUGCUGGGCAUUGUCUGUUUACAACUAAAGCAGAUUUUUUCUUUUGCUUUUGUCUUCAAAUGUGAGCUUUUCAGAGUCUCUAGUGCAACCAUAUUAGUGUUUUAGAUGCUUCCUGAUUAUAGUUAUUUGUGCUUAUGUAGUCAGAAUUUCCCCCAAAGUGUUUCUGGAUAUGGAUUUACACCUCAGUUCUGCCUGGGCUGCUAACUAGCUGAGGGACCUUGUGCAAGUCAUUCACCCUCACUGAACAGGUAAUAGCACUGCCCUACUUAGCUCUGAGGGUUGCCAUGAGGACCAAAUGAGUGGUAGUCACAAAGAUGCUUUGCAGGGCAUAAUGGACCCCACAUAAUGCACCCCACAAUGAAAUGUGUUAUUCAGCUCCUAUUUUUCUUUUGCUUUUCCCAUCAAGAAGAAUGCUCUUCAGAUUGGACAGUGUAAAACCAGCAUCAUUAAAAAAAGAACUAAAGCUCAAAAUAGGAGCAAAGAUAGAGAGCAGCUCAGUCUUUAAAGGAACUCAAUCCCUGAGUGUCUCAGAACCAUCAGGCCUGAUCUGCAGAGCUGUGAUGGAUGUGUCAGGCUAUGUUAUGUCAGGGACCAGAGUAGGUUCCAUGGAGGGAGAACAGGAGGGCCCGUGAGGGCUUUGGCCACUGUCACUGUGAGAAACCGUUGAAAAAAAAACUAUGAAAUUUAGAUAAGAAAAGACUCAAAAGAUGGCACACACAUGCCACUGCCUGCUUAGAAUUAGAGAUUCCUCCAAGAACCUCACGAUUUGUGGAACACCUCUCCCCACCCCACACCCUGCCCUGCCCCCCAGGACAUUCCUCAGAAUCUCACCAUCUUCCCAGCAGGCCCCUCAGCAGUAAUGGGGAAGAAGUAGACAGCCAAGGAAGAGUAGGAUCCUUGCUUCUGUGAUUCCGCCCAUAGCCACCCCGUGGGUCCCCCGCCGUCUGUCUGGGUUCAGUUUGUGCCUCCACACUUAUAAACCGUGUGACCUUGGGCAGGGGCUGUGUCUUGAAUUUCCCAUCAUAUGGAAAUGAUAUCUUGUUCAUAGUCUUGUUACAGAGUUUAGACAAGAUGACAUAAAGUUCUUAGCACGAGUUCUUCUCAAAAGACGCUAGGUUGUUUUUGUUUGUUUGUUUUUGCCUUCUCCAUUUCCUGUAGCCCUAUCUAUUUCUGAUUAUAAAAAGAGGACUGUUUCAAAAAAUUAAACAUAAGCUUACCAUAUGAUCCAGCAAUUCCACUUCUGGUGGUAUACACACCCAAAAGAAUUGAAAGAAUUGAAGGCAGGACUCCAACAGGUAUUCAUAUGCCCAUACUCAUAGCAGCAUUAUUCACAGUAGCCAAAAGGUGGGAACAACCCAGUGUUCAUCCGUGGAUUAAUGGACAAGCAAACUGUGGUCUAUCCUUACAGUGGAAUAUUAUUCAGCCUAAAAAGGAAGGAAAUUCUGACACAUGCUACAACAUAGAUGAACCUUGAAGACACUGUGGUAAGAAAAAUAAGCCAGACACAAAGGACAAAUACUGUAUGAGUCUACUUAUAUGAAGUAUUUAGAGUAGUCAAAUUCAUAGAGAGAGAAAGUGGAAUUAUGGUUACCGGCGGGGCAAGAAGAGAGGGUAUGGAGUUUCAGUUUGGGAAGAUGAAAAGAGCUCUGGAGAUGGAUGGUGGCGAUGGUUGCGCAACAGUUUAAACAAUGUCACCAAACAGUACGCCUAAAAAUCACACAUAGAUAAAAUAUACAUUUUAUGUUAUAUAUAUCUUACUACAGUUAAAAAAUUGCUUACACGACAAACAUAUUUUAAUUUCAGUUAUGACAUAAUUUUAGAGAUAUUAAAAUGUGAAAAUCACAUAAAUCUUUAGAAUAAAAAGAAUAUGGUUUUUAACACUCAAAAAAAAAAAAGAAA